AGACCAGCCCUGUCCUCUGCGCCCCCCACCUGUCCACACUCCAUCAUGUGCCACACCAGCCACUCUUCGGGCUGCCCAAUGGCCUGCCCUGGCUCCCCGUGCUGUGUCCCCAGCACCUGCUACCCACCCGAGGGCUAUGGGACCUCCUGCUGCUGCUCAGCCCCCUGUGUGGCUCUGCUGUGCCGGCCCCUGUGUGGGGUAUCCACCUGCUGCCAGCCAGCCUGCUGUGUGCCCAGCCCCUGCCAGGUGGCCUGCUGUGUGCCUGUGAGCUGCAAGCCUGUUUUGUGUGUGGCUUCCUUCUGCCCAACCUCUGGGUGCUGCCAGCCCUUCUGCCCCACCCUGGUCUAUAGACCUGUCACCUGGAGCACCCCCACUGGCUGCUGAGCAGGUGGCCUCCUAUGACCCUCGUAGGUGCGAGGUCAGAAGCCAGCAGGCUCUCUGAACUCC